AGCACAGUCCCGCGGACGGCUGAGCGUGUGGCUGCAGGAGCUUCUGUGGGAGUACGGUCAUGAGCCUUUUGCUGUACUAUGCCCUCCCUGCCCUGGGCAGCUAUGCCAUGCUCUCCAUCUUCUUCCUGCGCCGGCCUCAUCUGCUGCACACGCCCAGGGCUCCCACCUUCCGCAUCCGCCUGGGGGCCCACCGAGGAGGAUCUGGAGAGCUGCUGGAGAACACCAUGGAGGCCAUGGAGAACUCCAUGGCCCAGCGCUCGGACCUCCUGGAGCUCGACUGUCAGCUGACACGGGACAGAGUGGUGGUGGUGUCACAUGAUGAGAACCUGUGCCGCCAGUCGGGCCUAAACAGGGAUGUGGGCAGCCUGGACUUCGAGGACCUGCCCCUCUACAAGGAGAAGCUGGAGGUUUACUUCUCUCCAGGCCACUUUGCUCACGGGUCAGACCGGCGCAUGGUUCGUCUGGAGGACCUGUUCCAGAGGUUUCCAAGGACACCCAUGAGCGUAGAGAUCAAAGGGAAGAACGAAGAGCUCAUCCGUGAGAUAGCAGGCUUGGUGAGACGCUAUGACCGUAAUGAAAUCACCAUCUGGGCCUCGGAGAAGAGCUCGGUCAUGAAGAAAUGCAAGGCUGCCAACCCCGAGAUGCCCCUGUCCUUCACAAUAAGCCGAGGAUUCUGGGUGCUGCUUUCCUACUACCUGGGGCUGCUGCCCUUCAUCCCAAUCCCUGAGAAGUUCUUCUUCUGCUUCCUGCCCAACAUCAUCAACAGGACCUAUUUCCCAUUUUCCUGCUCUUGCCUGAACCAGUUAUUGGCUGUGGUUUCGAAAUGGCUGAUCAUGAGGAAGAGUCUGAUCCGACACUUGGAGGAGCGAGGGGUGCAGGUGGUCUUUUGGUGCCUUAAUGAAGAGUCGGAUUUUGAAGCAGCCUUCAGCGUGGGAGCCACUGGCGUCAUAACGGAUUAUCCCACAGCCCUGCGGCACUACCUGGACAACCAUGGACCAGCUGCCCGGACCUCCUAAGUCCAGAAGCCUCGAGGUCUCCUGUUUCUCUUCCUGAAAAAUAAAUAUUUGCCUUUCGAUCA